GCAGAGCCAGGCUUUGCCUGGGUCAGUAGGAGGAGCAGGGAAGAUGAGGAGGCUGGGGAAGAUGGGGAGGUCCUGGCUCUUUUGCAGGGAUGGAGAGGCUGGUGGAAGGAGAAAUCAGCCGACCCCCUUGGGUCAUCUCCAGUUGCAAGAUGGCGUGGCCCUUGCCCAGGGUGCUGCCCUCCCUGUUGGAAUCCAGGGCAUGGGGCUAUGGCCCGACCACGUGUGCUCAGGGCAAAUGUGCUCAGGUCUAUAUCUCAGAAAGGGCUUGCAGCCUGCUUAGGCGUGUGUACCCAGGCUUAAAUCUUGGUGGUCUCUCCCUAGGGUCUUAAUUGGAGGAGCAUCAGGAAUUGGGAAGCUUUGAACCAUGUUUGGGUACAUUUGUACCCAAACGUCCUUUAAGCCCUUGGUAGAAACUGCAUUCGCGUAUCAUCUCCCUUCCCCCCAACCUUCCUUCCCUGAGGGUUUUAAAAAACACUUCCCAUUGCUUUUACCUUUCCAGCAAAUCUGGCUGCAGCUUGGAUGGAUAGCUUAUCUUCCUUUGCAGGUUUCUAGGGGAGAGUUUAACCAGGUAUCAGGUGUGAGCAUGGCUCUGAUUUUGUAUAAACCUGAGGAUCGAGGAAGAGAAGCAAAAUCUAUUCUCACACCUCUGGGUGGUUAAGGUUUUGCCUUGUUUAGAGCAGGGAGGAUGGAUUUCUCAAAGACUCUUCUGUUCCCUUCUACUUUGGCUUUGGUUCAGAGCUGCAGGCAGCUCCAGAAUCUUCCUGAAGAGCUGGGUGCUGUGUGAUUUGAAGGGCUGCAGGAAGUCAUGGGUGUGUAGACCUCUGGCUUUUCUCCUAGGUGGGCUGCAGGAAGUCAUGGGUGUGUAGACCUCUGGCUUUUCUCCUAGGUUGGCUGCAGCCACCUCCAAGGAGAUGUGUUGCAAAGUGGUGACAAUGCCCCCUAGGAAGGGUUUGGAUAAGGGUCUCCCCACUCAUCCACUGCCUAACUUUUGCAGCUACCAGGGAAUGCUCCUCCUGACUCCCUGGGUUUGUUGUCAUCUCCCUACCUGUUUGUAGGAUGUGUGGGCAUUUUUUUCCAACCUGCAGAAUCCCUGGCAGGAAUAGGCUCUCUGGGCCUUGUUUGUCGUGGGGCUACUGGUGUUGCAAUGGGCUGUCUCUCUCGAGUGUCUGUUUCCAGCUCCACUCUGGAAAGAAAGGGGCCAACGCCGACUCUAGGCCGGCCUGCUCUGUAUUCAUUCAGCUCCAGCUCAACUUGAGCAAUCAGAGCCAGGGUUGAGGGCAAGCUACAUUCUUUUCUGCCUUUCUGCUGCAGGAUGCAGUUUGCUUUUUUUCCAUGCGAAUGAAUUAUGUUUGAAACCGAAAUGGGAGGAAGAGAAAAAUGGAGUGAGUGUAUAUGGGUAUGUGUGUGUGCAUACCUAUAUAGGCAGGGGAGGGCAGCAGGCACAUUAUUUUUCCAUUUUCCUUUAAUUAAGGCUCUGUGGAGGUGUGUUUGAAAACAGAGGGUCUCCUAUGCCUUUGAGGAGGGUGAGAACACUGUUUUGGCUGCGUCCCGGGCCAUAUGCAGCGUAUGGUGGCCAAUGAAACCGGGCCUGGCUCAUUCUGUUGCUUGUCUUGGCAGUCGGUUCCGUGGCUUGUAUUACCAGCUCUGGAACUUAGGGGCUGCCAAGCUCCAUGUGCCUGUGUAUGUGUGUGUGCGUGUGCAUGUGUGUGCACAUGCGUUCUUGUGUGUGUGUGUGGUUUGGCCUCUCGGAACUCAGCAGAGACAAAUGCCUUAGCGACCCAGUCUUGGAAUUUUCAGACUGUGUUUCUUUACUUAUUGCUGGCUGUGGGAGGCCUGGCCAGAGCCCACCAUUCUUAGUUGUUGUUGUUUUUUAGUCUGUUUUCUUGCUGCAGCCCACGGGAUUUAGUUGCAGAGCUCCAUUUGCAAAGCUUCAGCUGGCCAGUGGCAUUUUUUAAAAAAAAGACCAGGGCGAUUAUCACACCUUGUGUGUGUGUCUGUAUUAGGUGUGGUAGUGUUAACCCCUGCCAGCCACCAAGGACCAGAGCUGGCGUGAAGUAGAAGGGAAAAUAGAAAGCUUGUCCAAUGGUUGUACGCUCCCAGCUUCCUCUUGCUGCCUGGGUUAAAGAUUCCUGGCAGAGAUAACUUCAUAUGUAUUUAUUGAGCGCCUACAUUAGGCAGAGGACAAAGCGAUGUUAUAGGCAAGGCCUUGGAAGCAUUUCUCUGGUCUCCAGGGAAGAGCAGGAGUUCCCUGGGGGUUGGUUCCAGGUUCUUCUAUGGCUGGGAUGGCUGUGCAGGGAUCACGGCUGCCAGUGUUCAGUGGCUUCUCUUGAACCCAGCUACCGCUCCUUGUCUUCUUAUGAAGCAGUGCAGGGAUGGAGUAGAGGGCACAGGAGAUGCUGGCUGUCUGCCUUGGGGCAGAAAUGGAAACCUAGUUCUUGAUGGCACCUUGUUGCCAGUGUCUGUGCAGCUGUGUUCUGGCCUGCAGGGUGGAGGAGACCUUAGAGGAAACCGAGGCCGAGGGCAGGUGCUGGGCCCCAUUUCUGCACCUUCUACCCAGCCCUGACCUGGCACCCUUUGUUUCUGUUCUGCAGUCAACUGCCAGGAUGCAAGAUGGUCCUGCCCCCUUGGGGUUUAGAGCUGGAAAGUGGGAGAGCGGAGAAUCCUCUGGGGAGAAUCCUCUUCAUGGCUGCAGGAAACAGAGACUAGUCCAGAAGGGACCUUGAGGGGUCAUCUGGCACUAGUGCCCCUCCAGGAAGGAAGGCCCUGGUGGCCACACUGACUUCACUCUUACUAUGUGCAGGCACUGUUCCAGAGCUGGGGACAGCCAUCUGAAGAGGGCCUUUUGCUGCUCGCCUUCACUCUCAGUCUUGGGGCCUUCCCCAUCAUCUUGCUUCUCGCCUUCUGGAUCUCCUCGACUUUUGGAAGCCGCGUGACCUACGUCAUUCAGAUUCCAAGAGAGAGGUCAUCCUGGGUGAUUCCUUAGCUCCAAGAAGAGGCUUGGUGGUUGAUUCUCCAAGAUUCAUGGUAGCAGGCUGGCCUGCCACUCCUCCUGCUAUGAUGCCUGGGCAGAUCCCGGACCCUUCGGUGACCACAGGCUCCCUGCCAGGGCUUGGCCCCCUGACCGGGCUCCCCAGCUCGGCCCUGACUGUGGAGGAGCUGAAAUACGCUGACAUCCGCAACCUCGGGGCCAUGAUUGCACCCUUGCACUUCCUGGAGGUGAAACUGGGCAAGAGGCCCCAGCCCGUGAAAAGUGAGCUAGAUGAGGAAGAGGAGCGAAGGAAAAGGCGCCGGGAGAAGAACAAAGUCGCAGCAGCCCGAUGCCGGAACAAGAAGAAGGAGCGCACGGAGUUUCUGCAGCGGGAAUCCGAGCGGCUGGAACUCAUGAACGCAGAGCUGAAGACCCAGAUUGAGGAGCUGAAGCAGGAGCGGCAGCAGCUCAUCCUGAUGCUGAACCGACACCGCCCCACCUGCAUCGUCCGGACCGACAGUGUCAAGACCCCCGAGUCAGAAGGCAACCCACUGCUCGAGCAGCUCGAGAAGAAGUGACCAUGGGCUGGGAGGAGGUGGAGGAGGAGGAAGAGGAGAAGGAAAAGUGACGAAGAGAGAGGAGGAGGGGGGCCCCAGAUGGCCCUUCCUUUGGUGCAUGAAAAACUGUACAAUGAGGUUCAGCACAGCCAGCAUCAGCCGAGCUUUUUUGUGAAACUCAGAUCAGCCACCCAGGAGGAAGAGCGGGCUGAGGAAACCCAGAGGGACCAAGCGCUGAGACCAAAGUUGACCCUCGGGUAGGGUUGUCCUGCCUGGGGCCCCACUUGAAGGAGGCAGGACAGAGGCACCGAGGCCAGGGAGACGCCCAACGAGGCAGCCCUGGGCUCUUCUCUGGCCUCUUCACCAGGGCACCCAUCCAAGGAACCUCCGAACAGCCAGGAAAAGCCAUGAGUUGCAACCAAAACGCGGCUGAGGAUGGAACUCAGAAUGAAACUGCAACCCACCUGCCCCCAGCCCUGCCCCUCGCCCUGAUGCGAAGCUGGAGAGGGGCGUGCUGCGGGGCCCUGAUGCCCCCACCCACCUCGGUCCAGCGCGGCCCUGCCCAGGAGGCGGCAGCCGGGCGCACCCUCGCCAGCCCUGCUGGAGUUUGCUGUGGGCACUGAGGCGCGGGCGCCCUUCCAAAGCACAUACUCACCGAAUGUUUACAGACUGGCUGUCCUGGCAGGGCUUUCAACUGCACAUGUUUUUUAUACUUUCCUUUUUUUUUUUUUUUUUAAUAUUUUUUACAAAAAAAAAGAUUUUAUACAAGCAAUAUAUAUAUGGAUUUCUAUAAUCACUCGAUGUGAUACAGUAUAAAUAUGCUAUGGUUUGUUUGUUAUGAACAGAUAGCCACCAGUUACGGCCGUUGUGUGUAACUCCUAAGUACUGUAGUCUCUGGGUGUCGGGGGUGGCCAGGGCGGGGGCGGGGUGCAUUUCCAUCCUUGUAAACCCUUCAUAGUACUCAGUCCUGUAUCGCUCAGUAAACAUUGCUCUUACUUACAUAGCCGCCUUGCGUGGUGUCUGCCUGGGGAAUGGGUGCAAGGCCCUCUCAGGGUCGGAGACUGUUUGGAGCCUCUGCUAUAGGCCUGUUCAUUUUCACAACAGCUCUCCUAUUUCACAGAUGAGGAAGCUAAGGCUCAGAGACAUUAAGCCACCUGCAGUUACUAUUUUGAGAGCAGUCAGAGUGUUCGCUCACUCUGCAGAUGUUUUCUGAGGGCCUGUUGUGUGUGCCAGGCCCUGAGAAUUCACUGGAGGAUGAAACAGACCUAAGUCUUGCCCUUGUGGGGCCUCCAGUAAGGAGUGAAUCCUGUGCUUGCUCCAUAAGUUGUCUCAUUUCGUCUUCAUGGCAGCCUUGCCAGGGAACAGCACUUGUCCCCAAUUCACAGAUGGCGAAUUAGAGGUCCAGGGAAUUAAACUCGCAGACACCAUUUGUUGAAGACUUAUUUUGUGACAAGCAGACAUAGUCUCUUCCCUUCUCACAAGAGCACAAACUAGGCACGAUUCUUCUCAUUUUACAGAUGGUUUAACUGAGGCUCAGAGAAGGUAAGCGACUUAUCCAAGGUAACCCAGCUAGCAAGGGAUAGAGCUGGUGUUUGAACUCUCCCUCCAGAGGCCUGUGACUCUCCUCCUGUCACCAACCCACUAUGAUUGUCCUCAUGGUUGAAUAGGAAGCUUAUGAGGCCACAGUUAUAGAUUUAGUUUCUGGGAAGGCUGGAUAGAGUUCCAGGUUGUCCCAUGAUCACAGAGUGAACCAACUACCCUGGUCAAUGUGUGUCUGACCCAGGGAAGGGUGUGGAUGGCUUCUCUGCCCCCUCACCUCGACAGCUGAAUCCCUGCCACCCAGGGCCGGAGCAGCUCAGUGGCAUUCACUCAGUGCCUGCUGUGUACCUGGCACUCGGCAGUUCUCAAGGCAUGUCACGCAUGAGGAAGGCGGGAGAGGUGUUUUUAGCUUCCUUGUAUACUGAAGCUUGCAAAGGCUACAGUUUACCCAACUAAACUUGACUCCUGCAUUCUAAUCAUGUGUUCUUUCUCCUCCAUCCCUGGACUUAGGAUAACUAGUUGCUGGUGAUGACUUCGUGUCAAGAACAGCAGUGAACCUGGGUUGCUUCCCAAAUUGUGGACGAGGCCUUCUGGGAUGGGCAGAAGUGGAGAAUGGUGAUUAACACACCUGUGAUCCCUCCCUCGCUCACUCCUCUCAGUUUCCCUCCACCCAACACACUUGGUGUGGACUCCCCUGCACCCCGCCCUAGAAACAGGACCUGGUCCUCUCACUGUCAGCUGUGGCAGAAGGUUGUGGCAGCGGGUUGCCUUCUGUCUCGGGGGUCUUGAGGCUGUCGGUCCGGACGAUGCAGGUGAGGCAGUGUCAGUUCUGCAUCAGGAACCCCUCGCGCUGUAAUCCUUUGAUAUUUUUCAAGCCAUGAGAAAAAUGAAGUGGACUUACCAGGGUCCCUCCAGUGACCUAGUGGAUGUUCUUACAGGACUGCCGUGUGCCACUGGCUGUGGCUUCCCUGGUCCUGUGCUUGGCCACCGGGAGCUGGCAUCUCCAAAAUAGAGCCUCCUUAGCCUGUGCAGGUGGGCUGUCUUCCAAAGUCACCACACCAGUGACUUGUGCUGUGCGGAGCCUUCCUCACCAGGACCACUGGCUGCUCCUGUGGCUAGAAGUCACAAUUAUAGGCUUCAUUGCAAGAGCCAGCAUUUGAGUUUCUUCUGGGCACCUGCCACUGUGCAUGUGUGACCUCAACUGCUUUGUGCACCCUGACUGGGGGGUAGGUGCUAGCGUUCCAACAUUACAGAUGAGAAAACCGAGGCACACAGAAGAGGUAACCUGCCCAAGGUCACAGGUGUUAGGUGGCAGAGCCAAGAUGUUAUUGUCAGUCUGACUUCAGGUGCAUAAAACCUGAGGCUGAGCCUCCCCAUGAGAGGAAAAAUGUGUUUGUGGUGUGACCUCAGUUGCCAGGGAACUUGUGCAGGAAGCCGGGAGAGAUGGCACAGACCCACCUGUGCUCACAGUACAUGUUAAGAAUUCCCAAGUCUCAGGCAAACCAUCUCCAAGGGUGUUCACAGAAGACACACCUUAAAGGCAAACGGGUUCAUGAUGUAAUCUUCUAUUGACUAGCUGUGAACCUCAUUUUUCUUAUCUGUGAAGUGGGAACAGUAAUAAUCCAAGUCUUUUUAUGGAGUUAUCAAGAUCAAAAAAGGAAUGGAUAUACAAAGUGUUUUGUGAAAUAAAAGCUCCCUAAAAUGGUAAUUAUUUUGUCCUCUGUUAGUGUCGGUAGUUAUUGAUAUCUACAUAGUACAGGUUAUUUAAAUAUGUUUUAUUCUGUAAAGAUGGGCUGCCAAGUUUGUGUUCUGACCCUGUACGUGGUCCCUAUGGUGUGAUGAAUGCCUGGGAUCGCAGACUCCUGGAUCUGUUCAGCUCCUGACUGGUCACAACCAGCCAUGCUGGAUGCAUCAUUCCCUCCCUGGGCCUCAGUGUGCCCUCCUGCCAGGUGGUCACACAUAAGACCUGUGCCACCUCUGCCCAGGGUUCCUAUGAGAAUCAAUCGAGUUGAUGAAUGCAACCAUGGCCUGAGAAAGACAAGACGCUUUAGCUAUCAGAUGGGCAGAAACAAGUAUGUGUUGGUAAGAAUAUGGAUUAAAGGUUGGGAGGCCAAGAUGGGUGGAUCAUGAGGUCAGAAGAUUGAGACCACCCUGGAUAACACGGUGAAACCCUGUCUCUACUAAUAAUACAAAAAAUUAGCCGGGCAUGGUGGCACGUGCCUGUAGUCCCAGCUACUCGGGAGGCUGAGGCAGGAGAAUCACUUGGACCUGGGAGGUGGAGGUUGCAGUGAGCCAAGAUUGCGCCACUGCACUCCAGCCUGGGUGACAGAGCGAGACUCCAUCUCAAAAAAAACAAAACAAAAAAAAUGUGGAUUAAAGGAAACUUAGAUAUGCUGCCAGUGAGAAACUGUGCAAAGCAAUUUGGAAAUAACCAGUAAAACUAAAGCUAAACGCAUCCUUUGACCUAGCAGUUUUCCUCCUAGUCUUGGGAGGAACUCUAGCACAGGGGCAAAAGGAAAUGUACAAGAAUGUUCACUGAUGGCUUUGUUUGUAUUUUUAAAAAGUUGAAAACAACCUAAAUGAUGAUCAGCAUAAGAACAAAUAAAUUGUGGUAUUUUCCUAAAAUUGAAUAUUACUCAACAGGUAAAAAAGAAUGAACCAGAGCUAUAUGUAUCAAUAUGGAUAAAUCUCAGAAACCUACUGUUGAGAUGGAGGGUAGGGGAGUGAACUGCGGAAGGAUACCACUUAUGUCAUAUUUCUAACUAAAUGUAUACGUUGAUACUUUAUUGUUUAUGGCUACACACACAUCUGGGUAAUAGAGGUAUAAAAGCCUGCACAAGAAUGCUGUCAAUAUCACAAUCAGUCAUAGGGAGUGCUCCUGGGAGGGCCGCGGAGAGGAGGGAACUAGGGAUGCCACUGCAAGGGUAAGUAGGACGCUGGACUUCAACUUCAACUAUACACAUAACAUUUCAUUUAUUUUUUUAAAAUCCCCAUCAAAUGUAGAAUGACAGGAUUUUUCAGAGGUGGGUGAUGUGUGCACAGAUGUGGGCUAUCUUCUCCACACUCCUCUGUAUAUUUGAUAUUCUUUGCAAUAAAAGAGAACAAGCCACAAUA